GGGCUCGCGGCUGCGGCUUCUGCUCAGGGAGGCGGAAGGCGGCGGCGGGAGCGGUCAUGGAGGCGGGCGCCGGAGCCGGCGCGGGAGCCGCGGGCUGGAGCUGCCCGGGCCCAGGACCCACAGUGACCACUCUAGGCUCCUAUGAGGCUUCCGAGGGCUGUGAGAGGAAGAAGGGCCAACGCUGGGGGUCCCUGGAACGACGGGGGAUGCAAGCUAUGGAGGGGGAGGUGUUACUCCCAGCUCUCUAUGAGGAGGAAGAGGAAGAGGAAGAGGAGGAAGAAGAGGUGGAAGAAGAAGAAGAACAAGUGCAGAAAGGUGGCAGUGUUGGCUCUCUGUCAGUCAACAAGCACCGGGGACUGAGCCUCACGGAGACAGAGCUGGAGGAGCUGCGGGCUCAGGUGCUGCAGCUGGUGGCAGAACUGGAGGAGACCCGGGAACUGGCAGGGCAGCAUGAGGAUGACUCCUUGGAGCUACAGGGGCUCCUGGAGGAUGAACGGCUAGCCAGCGCCCAGCAGGCAGAGGUGUUCACCAAGCAGAUCCAGCAGCUCCAAGGUGAGCUGCGUUCUCUACGGGAGGAGAUUUCCCUGUUAGAGCAUGAGAAAGAAAGCGAACUUAAGGAAAUAGAACAGGAAUUGCAUUUGGCCCAGGCUGAGAUCCAGAGUCUGCGGCAAGCAGCAGAGGAUUCCGCAACUGAACAUGAGAGUGACAUAGCAUCCCUGCAGGAGGAUCUCUGCCGGAUGCAGAAUGAACUUGAAGACAUGGAACGCAUUCGGGGAGAUUAUGAGAUGGAGAUCGCCUCCCUCCGUGCAGAAAUGGAAAUGAAGAGCUCUGAACCAUCCGGUAGUUUAGGUCUCUCAGAUUACUCUGGGUUACAAGAAGAACUGCAGGAGCUGCGGGAACGCUACCAUUUCCUGAAUGAGGAAUACCGGGCCCUGCAGGAGAGCAACAGCAGCCUCACGGGGCAGCUUGCAGAUCUGGAGAGUGAGAGGACACAGAGAGCAACAGAGAGAUGGCUGCAGUCCCAAACACUGAGUAUGACGUCAGCAGAGUCUCAGACUUCAGAAAUGGAUUUCUUAGAGCCUGAUCCUGAAAUGCAGUUGUUACGGCAGCAGCUACGGGAUGCUGAAGAGCAGAUGCAUGGCAUGAAGAACAAGUGUCAGGAAUUGUGUUGUGAGUUGGAAGAGCUACAGCAUCAUCGCCAGGUCAGUGAGGAGGAGCAGAGGCGGCUGCAGAGGGAGCUCAAGUGUGCUCAGAAUGAGGUGCUUCGGUUUCAGACCUCCCACAGUGUCACCCAGAAUGAGGAGCUGAAGUCCAGACUCUGUACCCUGCAGAAAAAAUAUGAUACUAGCCAGGAUGAGCAGAACGAGCUCUUGAAGAUGCAGCUGCAACUUCAGACUGAGCUCCGGCAGCUCAAAGUCAUGAAAUCCACACUUGUAGAAAACCAGAGUGAGAAGGAGUUACUGUGCCGGCUGCAGAAGCUGCACCUCCAGCACCAGAACGUCACAUGUGAGAAGGAAAAGCUGCUGGAACGGCAGCAGCAGCUGCAGGAGGAGCUGCAGUGCCAUGAGGCAGAGCUGCAGCACCUCAGGGAUACGGUGGCCUCCUUCAAAGAGAGCAAUGAGAAGGACACAGAGACGCACGCUCAGCUUCAGGAGAUGAAGCAGCUGUACCAGGCCAGCAAGGACGAGCUGGAGCGGCAGAAGCACAUGUAUGACCAGCUGGAGCAGGACCUCCUGCUCUGCCAGCUGGAGCUGAAAGAGCUCAAGGCCUCCCACCCCAUUCCGGAGGACAAAGGAAAGUGUGCUAAUAAGUGUGACACACUGCUGUCCAGACUGACAGAAUUGCAGGAAAAGUACAAGGCCAGCCAGAAGGAGAUGGGGCAGCUGCAGAUGGAGCAGUGUGAGCUCCUGGAGGAUCAGAGGAGGAUGCAGGAGGAGCAGGGCCAGCUGCAGGAAGAGCUGCACAGGCUCACACUGCCACUGCCAAAGAGUGGCCUCUUACUCAAGAGUCAGGAGCUACUCACCAAGUUAGAAGACCUGUGUGAGCUGCAGCUGCUCUACCAAGGCAUGCAGGAGGAACAGAAGAAGCUGAUACAGAACCAAGACUGUGUAUUAAAAGAACAAUUAGAGAUCCACGAAGAGCUGCGACGUUUCAAAGAGUCUCAUUUCCAGGAAGUGUUGGAGAAUCCCGAUGAUUCCAAAUUGGCUAAGUCCUCCAAAUGUAAUCGAAACAAGCAGCCAAGAAGCCAGGCCCAACAUGCCCAGAGGCCAGAUUCAGAAUUGGGGCAGGAGAUACAGGAACUAAUACAAUCCAAGCUGCUCAUGGAGCAGAUGCAGGCCCUGCAGGUGAUGUAUGACGCCGGUCAGGCGAAGCAGGAGCUCUUGCAGCAAGAGCAAGGGAGGCUCCUAGAGGAGCGGAAGAGGCUGCAGGCAGACUUGCAGCUCUGCCUGGAAGAAAUGCAGCUGCUUCAAGUCCAGUCCCCUUCUAUAAAAAUGAGCCUUGAGUCCUACGGGAAGAGCUAUGGUAGCAUGGUCCCCAGCAAUGAGAACUGUCGCAAGACUUAUGAUACCACUGUGGAUGACAAUGAGAGCUAUUACAAGAGUUACACCAGCACCCAGACCAGCAGCAAGAGCUUUCUCAAGAGCUAUGACAGCAGCACCAGUGCCAGUGAGGCCUAUGGGAAGAGUUACUGCACUACCAGCAACAGCAGCAUUACCUAUAAGAAGAGUUACGGCAGCACCAGUAGCUCUGACACCUGCCAGAAGAGUUUUGUCAGCAGCUGCACUGACGAGGAACCUGCUGAGCCUGAAGACAUGGAGCGCUUUGAGGAAAUGGUUGUGAAAGUGCUGAUCAAGCUGCAGGCGGUGCAGGCCAUGUACCAGAUAAGCCAGGAGGAACACAGCCAGCUGCAAGAGCAGAUGGAAAAGUUACUGGCCAAGCAGAAAGACCUGAAGGAAGAGCUGGAUGCCUGUGAAAGGGAGUUCAAGGAGUGCAUGGAAUGCCUUGAAAAGCCCAUGGCCCCCCAGAACGACAAGAAUGAGAUCAAAGAACUGCAGACCAAGCUGCGGGAGCUGCAGCUGCAAUACCAGGCUAGCAUGGAUGAGCAGGGGCGGCUUCUGGUAGUGCAGGAGCAGCUGGAGGGGCAGCUGCAGUGCUGCCAGGAGGAGCUCCGCCAGCUCAGGGAGAAGAGGCCUUCUGUUGUCAAAGAAGCCCGGGGGAAGAAUGCUAAUAAGAACAUGAACAAGAAUGCCAAUGGGGUUAAAAUGAAAAAGGUGACCAAGCCAUGCUCGGAUACUUCUGAGAGCGACCUUGAGACCAGAAAGAAGAUCAGGAGGAAAAUGAAGAGGACAAAGAGGAAGAGGAGAAGGAAGAAGACAGUGAAGAGGAGGAGGAUGACGCCGACUCUUCCCUUGAAAGUCCCGAAGAAAAUAACCCCCUCAGACUUUCCGAGAGCAAAAAGAAGUCUUAAGGCACUACGGGUGAAACCCAAAGAGUUCAGCCACAGCCUUCCACUACCUCAGACCCAGCCCGGCCCAAUCAGAGGGAGAGGAAGAACUGCUGGUGAAGGGUUCUCCUGGUGGGGCCUGUUAUCCCCAGAGCUCCAGGAGGCCCCAACAUGCACCUGUGCAGCCAGGACCUGAGGGAGCACAGUGUGGUAGAAAGCGUGGCUGCCAGGCGGUCAGAAGAACUUGGUUGAGUCUGUCUCUACUGACAGGCGUUGUCCCAGGGAGCAAAAUGCACACUCUGAGCUCUAGUUUCUUCAAAUGUAAGCAAAGGAUGAUCGAACCUCUGCCCUCCUCACAGGUUUUUGUCAGGACCAGAUGGGUUGAAGUAGAUGAAAGUAUUCUAUAAAUUAUAAAAUACCCCAUCAUUAAUAAAAAGAGCACGCACUUACAAAAUGCAGUCUUAUGUGUCAGGCACUGUUCUAAUCACUUACGUAUAUUAACUGAUUUAAUCCUUGCAACAACCCCAUGAAGAAGCUACUCCUAUUUUUUUUUAUAUAUGAUUAAACUAAGGCAUAGAGAAGUUAAGUAAAACAGCCAGGAAGCUGCGAGUCAGAUUAUAAGGACUCAAUAUUAGCAACAAAUAAGAUUCCAGUCUUGCUUCCCUUUAUUGUCUCUCCUCAUUUUGAGCAGUUUCUCUUCAUUGGUCCCAAGUAGGAAGACACCAUACUUGUGUUUAGGCAACCUCAGAUCACAUUAGCUCUUUAGGUAACUAAUAUAUUAUUUAUUUAUUUCAUGUAUUUUUUAUAAGCCCCUCUGCAGAUUGUGUAUGCUAAGCGUCCUCUCCCCAUUCUGUACCUGCAUUUGAUUUUGAGGCUUCAAAGGCAGAAUUUUCCAUUCUUCCCUAUUAUAGUUCAUUGUUCUUACCUUAUAAGGUUUUGUGUGUAUGUGUUUUUAAUCUUGACCCUGUGGUUUUAAAAUAUUCACUUCCUCUGCCACCUUCACAUCAUCUACAGGGGUGGCAAGCCCUCCUUCCCUGUCUUCAUCUACAGAGGACAGAGUGAGGACAGAGCCUCUAGAGUGUCGUCUCUUGGGGUUCUUUUAUUCAGCUCAUUGGUCACUUACCUGCCAUUCAACAAACUGUACUGUCAUCCUACCCUUAUUUCUGCAUAUUAUCUGCAAAGAUCAUAGAAAAUUCUGUCAAACAACUCAACGUCCAAAAACAUGAUUCCGGUGAUUUGUCACUUAGGUCACCUAGUUUAAAAGGAGAGUUUGACACGACUUCCCCUUUGGGACACCCACACCAGCCCUUUCCCCAUCCCAUGUAGAAGCUUGCCUUUGCCCAGUGUGAGGUGCACGGGUCACAUUUAAGGAUUUCAGCUCCUCCCUCCUUUAAGAACACCAGACUAACAUUCUUAGCAAUGCACAUUAGGAUAGAGGCAUCUGAGCAUAUAAAUAUUUUUUUCUAGCUAGCUCCCUUCUUAGUUUUUGUUUUUGGUUUUAGAGACAGGGUCUCGCUCUGUCACCGAGGCUAGAGUGCAGCGGCAUGAUCAUGGCUCACUGUAACUUUGAACUCCCGGUCUCAAGCGAUCCUCCUCCCUCAGCCUCCGGAUCUCUUGGUUUUCUUACAUGAGUUACUCUGUAUAUCCACCUGUAACAUUGCUUGGCUUUCCAUUUCAUACCUUCUGUUGUUCUUAGUAGCUAUUUCUAUAAGCUCAGGAGAUUUUCUUUGCUCUUUAGCAGGCUUAAAGUCCUCUUUUUAGAUCAAUUAUCAUCUGAGAAAAUGUGUUCUUAGCAUUAAUGGGCUAUAUUCCAUUUUUACUUGAAACCAUCCUUCUGUUACCUAUGCCAUAGCUUAUGACUCAAAAUCCAAAUUCUACCUUUCAGUUAGUAGAGUAAAAAAGUAAUAAAAAUAAAACCUAUUUCCCCAA